AGAGUGGGGCACAGCGAGGCGCUAGGGGGAACGCUGGCCUCUGAAACUAGCUCUGGGACCGGGGUCUGCGGCCGGCCCCUAGCUGGCCCCGUCUCCCAUCCCCAGAAGGGUAUUCACUGGGGAUUCUGAGCUUUGGCUACUCCAGUUUCCCACGACACGUGAGUGUGAGGGGCGUGGAGGAGGAGGCGGGCUGGGUUGCGCUCACACUUAAGCGUCUGUGACAGGAGCCGGAAUCGCAUUCUCCCUUGACCAUGGUUCUAGCCAAAGAUCUGGCUGAGGAGCCCUAAGGGUAGAAUGGAGGCGGAGGCAUGAGAGCGGAGAGUCACGGAGUUCCGAAAGGUGUGAGGGAGAAAGGACUUCCAAGACCAGAGAGGGGAUUUACGAUAUUUAGAAAGCAGGGAAAGGAAAAUACCCCAAGUAUGGAGUCCGUUGGAGGUGUUGGUGGAUUUAUUUGUAGGAGGAAUUUUGGCCUGCAUCACGGUGGGAGGUCAAGUGGCAUCAUUUGGAGAGGGUAUGGCUACAAGCGCUUGGAAAGUCGGGACACUAGACAGAGCGAGAAUUUCUGGCACCCUGGGAGAGCUUUGAGGGGGAUGCGACUGUGGUGUGGAUAAGAAUGGCUGAUGGACGGAUUAUCUUGUGUUCCUCGUUGUGGGGAGCUUCCGCUCUUGGGACAUAGCCGCUACUUGUCUGAGGCUCCUUCUCUCUUGAGUUCUUUCAGCAUUAGGCCUUUUAGCCAAUUGAGGCUGCUUUUCUAAACAUGUAGGCUGCUGGAGAAAAAGGGAUAAGGACUGCUACAUCAGAAAGGAGCCAGCGGGAAGACAGUAGAAAUUCCACUGGUAAAUGGCCAUGGCUGUCUUAACAGAUGGGGAAGUGAGUGCUACAGAGGCCCAGUGGUGUAAGCUGCUUCCCAGUUGCUGGCUUAGUCAUUGGCCACCCUAAUAAAGGAUAAUUUUUAGCAUUGCCAAAUAAAAUAGAUCUGUCGUUAGAGAAUAAGAAAACUGAAAGAUUUUUCAAGAUCAUAAAAUCCUGCUCCUUAUUUCCAAAGUAUAUAGACAAACUCUUGUACCUUGAGAAUCUAAUUGUAGCAUAUUAAAAGGGGGCUACUGGGCCCUUCCAUUUCAUUCUCUUCCUGAUUGUUGCACCCCUAUGUUUAUAAGUUUUCCAGCAGUUAUCUUUAUGCCACGAAUCGUCUAAAUUGCCCCAGUAACUUCACACACAUUUAAUAUCUGUGUAAUGUACAGCAAGUAAUUUAACAAGUAAUUCUGUAAAGCAUCAGUUUUCUCAUCUGUGAAGUAUGAAAAAUUAUACCUAUUUUCUGGGUUGUGAAGAUGAAUGAACAUAAUCUAGGGAAAACAUUUAGCGCAUAUGCCACUGAAUUAAAGAGAAGCAGCUUAAAUUUAAAGACAAGCCUUAAGCAGGAAAGAAGAAUACAGUAUAAAUUUAUUAUCCUAACUUUUUGAAUAAUAAGCAAAUGAAAGAUAGUUCAACUCAGCUAAUGGCUGAGGUGUUUAACCUUUCAUCCCUUCCUAAUUUUGUGAGAUUCCUUGUUCUAAUUUAGGAAAAGAAAUCAACUGUCAGUUUUUAAUUAGGUCCUGAGAGACUGGAAAGGAAAAUGGCAGGCUAAGUCAGUCUAGAAGAAGGAGUCUCCUAUUUCUUUUUAGUGAGUCAGCUGGUCAAGUUGUGUGUUGAGCAGUGGGUUAACUUAGGGAAGGUGGGAGUUGGAGGUCUGAGUUCUUUAUUUCACCUCCUAUUCAGUCAACUGUGUGAGGAAUCACUUCCCCUUCACUUCUUAGUAGAAAAAAAAAAAAACCCACAGUUUUGGCUGUCUACUCUCAUCUCCAAAAAAUUGUUAUGCACAUAGUGGAAAUAUACAUGUAGUUGUUCAACACAGACCAUGAGCUCUGGAGCUAGACUCUCUGGCUCACUCCACUAGCUGUGUCUCAGUUUUCUUACUGGUAAAAUAGCAACAAUAAUUGUAUUUACUCAUAAGGUUGUGAGGAUUAAUUAGUUAAUUAAUAUAUGUUAAGUGCUUUGAACAGCACCUGGCCCAAGGCAGUAGUCUGUUGUUUCCUGCUGUUGUGUGGUUUCAGUGCAUUAAAUGUGUUAUGAGGGCCUUGGACCUCUUGGUUAGCUAUGAUUAUUCUAUGGAAACUACCAUAAUAUUACAGUAGAGAAUUGAUGUUUGGGGUACAGGAAGUCAGGUAGACAAUUUCCCGGGAUUUUUUGCUUUAGUGGGGUGUGGGAAGUGGAAGGUCAGAUGUUAGGUUGUUUAGGGGAAUGGGGAAAGUGCAUUCACGGCCAAGGUUGGAGCUUCCAUUUUCCCAUCUUCAAACUCAUUAGUACCCAUGAAAAUUCUGCCUGUUUCAAGUUUUAUAUUUUAAAAAUGAGGUGGAGUAAGUGGACCCGCAUGAAAAAGAACUAGAGAACUUUAAAGAAUAUUCAAACCAAAGUCCAGACUUGCAGCGUUUUUUGUAAGUGAGAAAAGUUUAGAAGAGUUAAAUCAGGAAAUUGUCCGUGAUACUCUUGGAAUAAACAAGUAGCAAUGGCCUGAGGGAUCAUUAACAGAUACCAGAGUAAAGUGUUUUGCAAGGGAUGUUCCCUUUCUACAGCUGCUGGAGGACUGGACUGCUACUACUACUCCUGGCUGUGGCAGUGAGAGAAUCCUGGCAGACAGAAGAAAAAACUUGCGACUUGGUAGGAGAAAAGGGUAAAGAGUCAGAGAAAGAGUUGGCUCUAGUGAAGAGGCUGAAACCACUGUUUAAUAAAAGCUUUGAGAGCACUGUGGGCCAGGGUUCAGACACAUACAUCUACAUCUUCAGGGUGUGCCGGGAAGCUGGCAACCACACUUCUGGGGCAGGCCUGGUGCAAAUCAACAAAAGUAAUGGGAAGGAGACAGUGGUAGGGAGACUCAACGAGACUCACAUCUUCAACGGAAGUAAUUGGAUCAUGCUGAUCUAUAAAGGGGGUGAUGAAUAUGACAACCACUGUGGCAAGGAGCAGCGUCGUGCAGUGGUGAUGAUCUCCUGCAAUCGACACACCCUAGCGGACAAUUUUAACCCUGUGUCUGAGGAGCGUGGCAAAGUCCAAGAUUGUUUCUACCUCUUUGAGAUGGAUAGCAGCCUGGCCUGUUCACCAGAGAUCUCCCACCUCAGUGUGGGUUCCAUCUUACUUGUCACGUUUGCAUCACUGGUUGCUGUUUAUGUUGUUGGGGGGUUCCUAUACCAGCGACUGGUAGUGGGAGCCAAAGGAAUGGAGCAGUUUCCCCACUUAGCCUUCUGGCAGGAUCUUGGCAACCUGGUAGCAGAUGGCUGUGACUUUGUCUGCCGUUCUAAACCUCGAAAUGUGCCUGCAGCAUAUCGUGGUGUGGGGGAUGACCAGCUGGGGGAGGAGUCAGAAGAAAGGGAUGACCAUUUAUUACCAAUGUAGAUUGCACUUUAUAUGUCCAGCCUCUUCCUCAGUCCCCCAAACCAAAGCUACACAGCCAGAUUUCUCAAGCAGUCUCAACUCCAGUCCCUCAUCUCACCCUUACUAUUGCUCUUGCUUUCCAGUUUGCUUUUGAUUUGCAUCUUCUCACUAGUAAAACUGCCUUCCCUUUGUUCCUUAUUUUCUGUUUUUUCUCUAGAGAGGUACAGUUGUAAGUCAGAGUUAAUAUAAUAGGGCCUGUGAAAACAGAGGCUUUUGCAUUGUCUCUUGACAUCAGAAGUUACAAUAGGCAUAUGGGCAAAAUGGUGUAGCAGGCUCACUGGCCGUUUGUUUUUUAAACACAUUUUCACAAGUUUUUGAGACACUGGAUUUCUUUAAUUAAAAAAAAAAUGCCAAGAAACAUUAUUUAUACAGGGUUGAUUGCUUUCAUGUUGUUAUUCUGUACCCUAUAGUAGCCUCCAUGAGAAUCUGGUAUUUCUUGCUGCUUGGAACUACUUUGCAGUGAUUACUUGGUUGCAGUCCAAGUACUCUCGUUUAGUCUGAGCCUGGAGAUGUUCUAGACUUGCUUCUCCCACCUCUGAGAUUAGGACAGGAAAAAUGUGAAAUUUCCCAAUUACAGGAUUAUACGGUACCAUCACAUCAUUUGUGGAAAUUGGGGUGACUGUAUAGCUGGGAUUGGGCUAAGGACUGUGGUCUUAUCUGUCCACAUACAGCCAAAAUGCCUAUCCAGAAAUCCAGUUCGUUGGAAAGGAAAAUUGGUACUCCUGUGCCACAGGGGUUCCAGAAAAGGGAAGUCACUUUACCUUGCGGUGGUGGGAUCCUGAUGUCUUUCAUCCAUUUGUAGUAAAAGCUGGUAAAGCUUUUCUUACUCCUGGUUCCCUACCAGUAUUUCUAAACAUGUCGCACUUUCUCCACAGGCAUGUGGUUUUGACCUUUUUUUCAAUCUUCUAGAAAGGGAACGGAAGCAGAAGUGGGACAUCGAGGGCUCUGCUGUCCUCUGCGCUGGGUGUGGAAUGCUGCUGCACCUGUCCCUUCUGCUGGCUCAGGGAAGUGUCUUCUUGCCCACAUUUCUGUGGGGAAAGGUUUUUAAUCCUCUGAUGCUUCCAUCUUCCUGUUUAGGCCAUGUGCCCAGAAACCUGGACUGAUCUUUCUUUAAUAGUGAACCCCUGGGCCACUGAAGAGUAACAUGGCUCCACUGGACACAAAAGAGGGAUGGAAUCAACAGGCAGGGGGCCUUUUAUAAGCCUUAGGAAAAGAAAAUGAAACUAUUUCAUCUUUGGACUUUUCAAUACUAUUGGAGUGAUUUUUUUCUUUCUAAACAGGGAAAAUAAUGUUACAAAAGCAUCUUUUUUGUUAUUUGUUUGCAUCCCUCCCCCACACCCUGGUGUUUUAAAAUGAAGAAAAAAAACCAUCACCUUUUGUACAAAAACUCUUAAUGAUUAAAAAACAAACAAAACAUA